AUCCGGUUUGCACGCCGGACCGGAGAGCGCGGAGGCAGCCAUGGUGCGGUUCAAGCACAGGUACCUGCUCUGCGAACUGGUGUCUGACGACCCCCGCUGCCGCCUAAGCCUCGAUGACCGAGUUCUGAGCAGCCUCGUACGGGACACGAUCGCCAGGGUGCACGGAACUUUCGGCGCAGCCGCCUGCUCCAUCGGCUUCGCGGUUCGAUAUCUCAAUGCCUAUACUGGAAUAGUGCUACUUCGAUGCAGAAAAGAAUUCUAUCAGCUUGUGUGGUCAGCUCUUCCCUUCAUCACAUACUUGGAGAACAAAGGACACCGUUACCCAUGCUUUUUCAACACAUUACAUGUGGGAGUCUGUAAGGUCGAGAUCUUUCACAAGCUGUUGACCACAGUAACUCAUAUGCCAGGUACAAUAAGAACAUGUCAGAAGUUCCUAAUUCAGUACAACAGGAGACAGCUGUUGAUCUUGUUGCAGAACUGCACUGAUGAAGGAGAGCGGGAAGCUAUCCAGAAGUCUGUGACAAGAAGCUGCUUAUUAGAGGAGGAGGAGGAGUCAGGUGAGGAGGCUGCAGAAGCAAUGGAGUGAACCUCUGCUCCCCACACAGCUGGCUACACUGCUCAGGCUUCAGGCCCACUUGUUGAACAGAACAAUCUGGGUAGCAACAGCAUCUUCCACAGUUUUCCAAACUGGAUAGCUGCCAACCAGCAGACAUUACCCACUUGAAAUGGAGUACUCAGUUAAACUGAAGUUGCCUUUACCUAGCAUUCCCUGGUGAAGUGUUGCAGGUUGUGAACUCUGUAGACAUCUUUAUUGCUUGGCUAAGAGUAGAUUUAAUAAAUGUAUCUGGUUUCCGUGGCAUUUAGCAUACUUAUAUUACAGAAAGGGCUUAUGGAGUCCAUGCUUGGCCAAGUCUCUGUUCUCUCUCUAUCCCUAGCCUUGGUGGGAAGACUGACUCCCUAUGUGGUACUAGUUAAACUUUUUUUUUUGAGACAGUCUCAGUCUAUCACCCAGGCUGGAGUGUAGUGGCCCAGUAUCGGCUCACUGCAACCUCCGCCUCCUGGGUUCAAGCAAUUCUCCCACCUCAGCCUUCCAAGUAACUGGGAUUACAGACGUGCACCACCACGUCUGGCUAAUUUUUG